ACAGUGCAUCGCUAUAAUUCAUUAAUACAUCAUAAAUCGUGAAGCACAGGGUUAUAACGACCACGAUCCACAAAUCAAGCCCUCCAAAAUCACCCAAAUGAGCUCGUACUUUGUAAACUCCUUCUCGGGGCGUUAUCCAAAUGGCCCGGACUAUCAGUUGCUAAAUUAUGGCAGUGGCAGCUCUCUGAGCGGCUCUUACAGGGAUCCCGCUGCCAUGCACACCGGCUCUUACGGCUACAAUUACAAUGGGAUGGACCUCAGCGUCAACCGCUCCUCGGCCUCCUCCAGCCACUUUGGGGCGGUGGGCGAGAGCUCGCGCGCCUUCCCCGCGCCCGCCCAGGAGCCCCGCUUCAGGCAAGCGGCUUCGAGCUGCUCCCUGUCCUCGCCCGAGUCCCUGCCCUGCACCAACGGCGACAGCCACGGCGCCAAGCCCUCUGCUUCGUCCCCCUCCGACCAGGCGACCUCAGCCAGCUCCAGCGCCAAUUUCACCGAAAUAGACGAGGCCAGCGCGUCCUCGGAGCCUGAGGAAGCGGCAAGCCAGCUAAGCAGCCCCAGCCUAGCUCGGGCGCAGCCAGAGCCCAUGGCCACCUCCACAGCCGCGCCCGAGGGGCAGACUCCGCAAAUAUUCCCCUGGAUGAGGAAGCUUCACAUCAGCCAUGAUAUGACCGGGCCGGACGGGAAAAGGGCCCGGACCGCGUAUACCCGCUACCAGACCCUGGAGCUGGAAAAGGAGUUCCACUUCAACCGCUACCUGACCCGGCGACGGCGCAUCGAGAUCGCCCACGCACUCUGCCUGUCCGAGCGCCAGAUCAAGAUCUGGUUCCAGAACCGGCGCAUGAAGUGGAAGAAGGACAACAAAUUGAAAAGUAUGAGCCUGGCUACAGCUGGCAGCGCCUUCCAGCCCUGAGCCCGCCCAGAGGAGCCCAGCGGCCCAAGAGCCCGUGCCACCCCCAGCCCUGGCCCCUCCAAUCCUCCCCGCUCUGCCGCCGCCCGCUGGGGACCGGUUCCCACAAGCCUGCCUCGCCUUGUGUUACGAUAUUUCGUUUGGUCUUAGGUCUUCCUGUGGCUCCCUCUCUCCUGGACUGGUUAUCUUGUUAUUAUUGUUAAUAAUAAUUAUUAUUAUUAUUUUCCUUCCAUGCUCCCAACUCCCUUCUGCUUGUCCCAAAUCCGCCAGUGUUUCUGAAUGUUUGUGUCUGUGGUUGCAGUCUUUCCCCCAGGAAAAAAAAAAAAAGAAAUUCGCAUGUUUAAUGUGAACUCUCCCCUCCCCAUCUGUGUUCUAACUUAUUUAUAAAAAGAUGAUCGCUGUAUUUUGAGUUUCAGCUGGAAACUUCUGUAAGGGGCAGCAGUUGAGGUGGGGUAGUGCCGCAGUGGGGUCAAGCUGAGCUGGCUUCGGAGAUGGAGUCCCUUUUCAUUCUCCUCCUCCUCCCUCCUCACUCCCUAGGCCCAAGUCUCCUAGGGGCUUGGUCCUAGGGUGGGAAGGGGCUAGGGAGGACCAAAGGGAUGGUAUUGAGAAGAGAGAAAGAAGAUAGUGAGAUUUAAGUUCCUGCUGCCUGGGUAGGCCCCACAAGGCCUGGUCUGGGAGUAUACGGAAACAAAAAUGAUCCUCAGUGCAAAAUGUCUUGUGUAUUUCUCUGUGAAUCCAUGGGUCUGGCUAGAGGGCCCAAAGCUUGUAAAUAUGGGGAUAGUCUGGGUCAGACCCAUCUCUCCCUUACCCAUCUUGCUUCCAAGACCAUUUGUAGUGAGCGAGUGGAUGCUGUGCUACGUGUGAAAUCUGUCUUUGCGGGGCCUGUCUCAGUGAUUCGCUUUUGGUAUUUGUUUGUAGCUUUCCUGGAAGUCAAAUAAAUGUUUCCCCCACUCCA